AAGCACUAAUCAAAUCUAAGACUAGUAAUAAGCAUCCUGAGUAAUGAGUGGCCUGGGCCGGAGCAGGCGAGGUGGCCGGAGCCGUGUGGACCAGGAGGAGCGCUUUCCACAGGGCCUGUGGACGGGGGUGGCUAUGAGAUCCUGCCCCGAAGAGCAGUACUGGGAUCCUCUGCUGGGUACCUGCAUGUCCUGCAAAACCAUUUGCAACCAUCAGAGCCAGCGCACCUGUGCAGCCUUCUGCAGGUCACUCAGCUGCCGCAAGGAGCAAGGCAAGUUCUAUGACCAUCUCCUGAGGGACUGCAUCAGCUGUGCCUCCAUCUGUGGACAGCACCCUAAGCAAUGUGCAUACUUCUGUGAGAACAAGCUCAGGAGCCCAGUGAACCUUCCACCAGAGCUCAGGAGACAGCGGAGUGGAGAAGUUGAAAACAAUUCAGACAACUCGGGAAGGUACCAAGGAUUGGAGCACAGAGGCUCAGAAGCAAGUCCAGCUCUCCCGGGGCUGAAGCUGAGUGCAGAUCAGGUGGCCCUGGUCUACAGCACGCUGGGGCUCUGCCUGUGUGCCGUCCUCUGCUGCUUCCUGGUGGCGGUGGCCUGCUUCCUCAAGAAGAGGGGGGAUCCCUGCUCCUGCCAGCCCCGCUCAAGGCCCCGUCAAAGUCCGGCCAAGUCUUCCCAGGAUCACGCGAUGGAAGCCGGCAGCCCUGUGAGCACAUCCCCCGAGCCAGUGGAGACCUGCAGCUUCUGCUUCCCUGAGUGCAGGGCGCCCACGCAGGAGAGCGCAGUCACGCCUGGGACCCCCGACCCCACUUGUGCUGGAAGGUGGGGGUGCCACACCAGGACCACAGUCCUGCAGCCUUGCCCACACAUCCCAGACAGUGGCCUUGGCAUUGUGUGUGUGCCUGCCCAGGAGGGGGGCCCAGGUGCAUAAAUGGGGGUCAGGGAGGGAAAGGAGGAGGGAGAGAGAUGGAGAGGAGGGGAGAGAGAAAGAGAGGUGGGGAGAGGGGAGAGAGAUAUGAGGAGAGAGAGACAGAGGAGGCAGAGAGGGAGAGAAACAGAGGAGACAGAGAGGGAGAGAGAGACAGAGGGAGAGAGAGACAGAGGGGAAGAGAGGCAGAGAGGGAAAGAGGCAGAGAAGGAAAGAGACAGGCAGAGAAGGAGAGAGGCAGAGAGGGAGAGAGGCAGAGAGGGAGAGAGGCAGAGAGACAGAGAGGGAGAGAGGGACAGAGAGAGAUAGAGCAGGAGGUCGGGGCACUCUGAGUCCCAGUUCCCAGUGCAGCUGUAGGUCGUCAUCACCUAACCACACGUGCAAUAAAGUCCUCGUGCCUGCUGCUCACAGCCCCCGAGAGCCCCUCCUCCUGGAGAAUAAAACCUUUGGCAGCUGCCCUUCCUCACUG